CUCCACCAGUUCAACCCCAGCAUGGCCGCGUCCACCAUGUCCGUCUGCUCCAGCGACCUGAGCUACGGCAGCCGCGUCUGCCUUCCUGGUUCCUGUGACUCUUGCUCCGACUCCUGGCAGGUGGACGACUGCCCAGAGAGCUGCUGUGAGCCCCCCUGCUGCGCCCCGGCCCCCUGCCUGAGCCUGGUCUGCACCCCAGUGAGCCGUGUGUCCAGCCCCUGCUGCCCAGUGACCUGUGAGCCCAGCCCCUGCCAAUCAGGCUGCACCAGCUCCUGCACGCCCUCGUGCUGCCAGCAGUCUAGCUGCCAGCUGGCUUGCUGUGCCUCCUCCCCCUGCCAGCAGGCCUGCUGCGUGCCCGUCUGCUGCAAGACUGUCUGCUGCAAGCCUGUGUGCUGUGUGUCCGUCUGCUGUGGGGAUUCUUCAUGCUGCCAGCAGUCUAGCUGCCAGUCAGCUUGCUGCACCUCCUCCCCCUGCCAGCAGGCCUGCUGUGUGCCCGUCUGCUGCAAGCCUGUCUGCUCUGGGAUUUCCUCUUCGUGCUGCCAGCAGUCUAGCUGUGUGAGCUGUGUGUCCAGCCCCUGCUGCCAGGCGGUCUGUGAGCCCAGCCCCUGCCAAUCAGGCUGCACCAGCUCCUGCACACCCUCAUGCUGCCAGCAGUCUAGCUGCCAGCCAACUUGCUGCACCUCCUCCCCCUGCCAGCAGGCCUGCUGCGUGCCCGUCUGCUGCGUGCCUGUGUGCUGUGUGCCCACCUGCUCUGAGGAUUCCUCUUCAUGCUGCCAGCAGUCUAGCUGCCAGCCAGCUUGCUGCACCUCCUCCCCCUGCCAGCACGCCUGCUGUGUGCCCGUCUGCUCUGGGGCUUCCACAUCAUGCUGCCAGCAGUCUAGCUGCCAGCCGGCUUGCUGCACCGCCUCCUGCUGCAGAUCCUCCUCCUCCGUGUCCCUCCUCUGCCACCCUGUGUGCAAGUCCACCUGCUGCGUGCCCGUCCCCUCCUGUGGUGCCUCUGCCUCCUCCUGCCAGCCCAGCUGCUGCCGCACGGCCUCCUGUGUUUCCCUCCUCUGCCGCCCCAUGUGCUCCCGCCCUGCCUGCUACAGCCUCUGCUCUGGCCAGAAGUCCAGCUGCUGACAGCCCUGGAUGUGAUCCGGAGUCCCUUCCCACCAGGGGCUGACCUCCCAGCUGCCCCAGCAAGCUCUGCCCUCUCUGGCUUUGACACCCUCAGAAGAUGGGGCAGGCUCUUUGUCUUA